ACAGAUCAAGACUCCGUCUCAGAAAAAAGAAAAUCAUAGCUGCCUUUUAAUAUAAAUAUCAUGUUCCCUUCCUCAGUUAAGGACAUACACCCCAGUUGAAAAAUCACUCUGCCUUUCCAGAUGCAGAAUCUAAUCUUUCCAAUAAGAUUCUGUUAACUGUUACUUUCUGUAGUUUGUAUUCCAAAACAAUAGGUAUAUCUUUCCAUUUUUUCAAUACAAAUUUUUAGAUUGGAUAUACCUUUCCAAACUGGACACACACUCACACAGUUUAGAAUUCCAGCUAUGGCUUCCUCUCAGAUUAUUAGCCCCUUUCUGGCAGGGAACAAUUCUUCCCAAGAAGGCCUGGAAGACAAAACCCUGGGCAGAGGCUGGUGGGGCCCACUCCUCAUCAGAAUCAUUGAAUCAUGACUGACCCCUAGUGGCGGCUUCUCUGUUUAACUGUCAGCCCAUGGGCUGGGAUGUGACCCCUGACCGUGCUGCAGAAGCUUCCACCCAUCCUGGGCCACCCCUGCCACCUGGGGGUGAAAGGCCUGUUCCUUGUCCUUUGAGCCCAGCAGGCCUCACAGACAUUCAGUAGAUUGGAAAGUCUAAGCAUGUGCUGGGCUGGGCUGGGCUCCGUCGCCCCUUUUUGGGGGGCAAGUGGGGUGCAUUCCAGUCCCCAGUAUCCCUGCUGUUUAUUCCCACCCUUCAGUGCACCACCCCCCCGGCCCCCCGGCCAUACACUCACAAGUACAAACACAGGCGCAGUCAUGGGCACACACUGCCCGGGACAGCACCAUUUCCAGGCUCUGUGGGGCAGUCUCCUUACAGGGAAGCUAAUGAGGCACUGAAGAAGGCUCAGGGGUCAGGGAAGACCUCUGUCGGAAAGAGGCUCCUAUACCUGGUUCCUCCUCUGACUUGCUGGGGGCACUUGAGAAAGUUUCUUCCCUCUUUGGUCUCAGUUUCCCCAGCUGAGAAAUAGGGGGUUGGGCUAAAUGGUCUAAAGUUCUGGGAACCUCUAACUCAAGCCCACAGCUGGUGGUCAAGAUGGGGGAGUCCCUCCGGGUCAGCUGAAUGCCUGAGAGGCAGGACAGGCCCAAAGGUGAGCCACCCGGGCACAUCAGGUGGGCUCGGAGCUGGAGCAUGAGCCCCACAGCCUGCAGAGCAGCCCUGCGCUUGGGAGCCCUGUCAGACCAGCCUAGUGGGACUUCAGAGAUGUGGGAUCCAGCCUCCCCUAGUAUUGCAGGGCUGGGGGAUGGGAGCUGCAGAUUCUGACCCCAGAGCUGCCUCAGACAUGCCAGAUGGGCUUGGGCAAGACACACCCCUCUCUAUGAAAUAAGUCAGUCCAAACAAACAUGCUAAAGAAGGGCUGUGGGAGGGACCCAGCUCUAGCCUGGGGCUACAGACUGGCUUCCAGGGUACUCAAGCAGCUGGCCUCUGGGAAAGGGGUCCUGGAUAUAAGAAGCAGGGCUCAGAAUCUAGGCCAAGCAUCCAUAGGACCCCCCUCUGGAGAGCCCAGGGCAGCCUGGGGGAGGGGCAGCAGGCAGCAGGUGCACUAGGAGCAUCUUUCACAAGGCACUAAAUAUUGCAUCUGUUCCAGAUAGGCAGCGAGUUGGAAAGUGGAUGAAGUCGGCAGGGUGGCGGCUGCUCCCCACAACCAGGAGUCCAGCCCAGCACCCACCCCUAAGUCCACCUCAGGCCUGCCUAAUUGGGUUGGUCUGUGCUCUGGGCCUUCUGGCCCUACCCACAGAGGAAGGGGUUUGGUGCAACUAGGUGAACUGGCCCUUGCAGGAAGAUGUAAUCGACUCCUGAGCCUGGCGAGCCAGGCAGCCCCUCACCAGCAUGCCCGCCCCCACCUCUCCGGCCCCUCUUAUUCCCUGAUCCUCCCACCUGCUUCCCUGCCCCGGCACUGUUUCUUCUGCUCAUUCUCAUCUCUUUUCCUCCUCCCAGGCUUGCCUCCUCAGAUGUCCUUGAGUCUCCUCUGAGUCUCCCUUUUUCCAAGCUGCCCCCUCUAUGCUUUACACAUUCUCCCUGAAGACACUAGAGUACACAAGCCCAAGUCCCUGAACCUCACCUUUACUCCCAGACAGGGAACUGCCGCGUGGCCAAUGCGGAGGAAAAGCUGAUGGACGACCUUCUGAACAAAACCCGUUACAAUAACCUGAUCCGCCCAGCCACCAGCUCCUCACAGCUCAUCUCCAUCAAGCUGCAGCUCUCCCUGGCCCAGCUUAUCAGCGUGAAUGAGCGAGAGCAGAUCAUGACCACCAAUGUCUGGCUGAAACAGGAAUGGACUGAUUACCGCCUGACCUGGAACAGCUCCCGCUACGAGGGUGUGAACAUCCUGAGGAUCCCUGCAAAGCGCAUCUGGUUGCCUGACAUCGUGCUUUACAACAACGCCGACGGGACCUAUGAGGUGUCUGUCUACACCAACUUGAUAGUCCGGUCCAACGGCAGCGUCCUGUGGCUGCCCCCUGCCAUCUACAAGAGCGCCUGCAAGAUUGAGGUGAAGUACUUUCCCUUCGACCAGCAGAACUGCACCCUCAAGUUCCGCUCCUGGACCUAUGACCACACGGAGAUAGACAUGGUCCUCAUGACGCCCACAGCCAGCAUGGAUGACUUUACUCCCAGUGGUGAGUGGGACAUAGUGGCCCUCCCAGGGAGAAGGACAGUGAACCCACAAGACCCCAGCUACGUGGACGUGACUUACGACUUCAUCAUCAAGCGCAAGCCUCUGUUCUACACCAUCAACCUCAUCAUCCCCUGCGUGCUCACCACCUUGCUGGCCAUCCUCGUCUUCUACCUGCCAUCCGACUGCGGCGAGAAGAUGACACUGUGCAUCUCAGUGCUGCUGGCACUGACAUUCUUCCUGCUGCUCAUCUCCAAGAUCGUGCCACCCACCUCCCUCGAUGUGCCUCUCAUCGGCAAGUACCUCAUGUUCACCAUGGUGCUGGUCACCUUCUCCAUCGUCACCAGCGUCUGUGUGCUCAAUGUGCACCACCGCUCGCCCAGCACCCACACCAUGGCACCCUGGGUCAAGCGCUGCUUCCUGCACAAGCUGCCUACCUUCCUCUUCAUGAAGCGCCCUGGCCCCGACAGCAGCCCGGCCAGAGCCUUCCCGCCCAGCAAGUCAUGCGUGACCAAGCCCGAGGCCACCGCCACCUCCACCAGCCCCUCCAACUUCUAUGGGAACUCCAUGUACUUUGUGAACCCCGCCUCUGCAGCUUCCAAGUCUCCAGCCGGCUCUACCCCGGUGGCUAUCCCCAGGGAUUUCUGGCUGCGGUCCUCUGGGAGGUUCCGACAGGAUGUGCAGGAGGCAUUAGAAGGUGUCAGCUUCAUCGCCCAGCACAUGAAGAAUGACGAUGAAGACCAGAGUGUCGUUGAGGACUGGAAGUACGUGGCUAUGGUGGUGGACCGGCUGUUCCUGUGGGUGUUCAUGUUUGUGUGCGUCCUGGGCACUGUGGGGCUCUUCCUACCGCCCCUCUUCCAGACCCAUGCAGCUUCUGAGGGGCCCUACGCUGCCCAGCGUGACUGAGGGCCCCCUGGGUUGUGGGGUGAGAGGAUGUGAGUGGCCGGGUGGGCACUUUGCUGCUUCUUUCUGGGUUGUGGCUGAUGAGGCCCUAAGUAAAUAUGUGAGCAUUGGCCAUCAACCCCAUCAAACCAGCCACAGCCGUGGAACAGGCAAGGAUGGGGGCCUGGGCUGUCCUCUCUGAAUGCCUUGGAGGGAUCCCAGGAAGCCCCAGUAGGAGGGAGCUUCAGACAGUUCAAUUCUGGCCUGUCUUCCUUCCCUGCACCGGGCAAUGGGGAUAAAGAUGACUUCGUAGCAGCACCUACUAUGCUUCAGGCAUGGUGCCGGCCUGCCUCUCCAUCACCAUCUCUCUCCACUUCCCCUUGUCCAGUUCCUCACACACUUCUAGAUUCUUCCCAGCUCAGAGGCUUGGCAUUUGCCAUAUCAUCAUCUUUUUUUUUUUCUUUUAAACGGAGUCUUGCUAUAUCGCCCAGGCUCAAGUGAUUCUCCUGCCUCAACCUCCCAAGUAGCUGGGAUUACAGAAAGCCGCCACCGUGCCCAGCUAAUUUUUGUAUUUUUGUUGGCCAGGCUGAUUUCGAACUCCUGACCUCAAAUGACCCACCUGCCUCGGCCUCCCAAAGUGCUAGGAUUACAAGUGUGAGCCACUAUGCCUGGCCUUCCCUAUCUUCUACCUGAACCUUCUUCCUCUUCCCCCAGGGCUUCCCAAGCUCUUUCCACAGCCACAUCAGUCAGGGCAUGGCUCCAAUCCAUUCUUUGCUCCAAUGUCACCUCCUCUGAGAGGCCUUCCCUAACCACCCAAUCAUUCUAAAGCAGCCUCCCUACAGUCACGUUACCCUGCCUCCUUCCUCGAGCACUCCUGUGUACCUGUCGCUCUUAUCUGGUGGCAUGUAUGUCAUCCACAGCUCACCCACUAGAGUGUGAGCUCCAUGAGAACAGGGACCUGCUCCUUCACAUUCGUGGUAGUAUCCCCAGGGCCUAGGACAGAGCUUGGCACACAGUAGGUGCUCAAUAAAUGUUUGUUGAAUGAA